GAGUUAUCAGAGGUGAGCCCGUGCUCUUCAGCGGAGAAGAUCCCCUACCUGGCCGCCGGCCACUUUCUGUGGGCCGUGGGGUCCUCAAGGAGACGGCCCUUGGGCUCAGGGGCUGCGUUUCCACACGCGCCUUUCCCAGGGCUCCCGCGCCCGUUCCUGCCUGGCCGCCGGCCGCUCCAACAGCAGCACAAGGCGGGACUCAGAACCGGCGUUCAGGGCCGCCAGCGGCCGCGAGGCCCUGAGAUGAGGCUCCAAAGACCCCGACAGGCCCCGGCGGGUGGGAGGCGCGCGCCCCGGGGCGGGCGGGGCUCCCCCUACCGGCCAGACCCGGGGAGAGGCGCGCGGAGGCUGCGAAGGUUCCAGAAGGGCGGGGAGGGGGCGCCGCGCGCUGACCCUCCCUGGGCACCGCUGGGGACGAUGGCGCUGCUCGCCUUGCUGCUGGUCGUGGCCCUACCGCGGGUGUGGACAGACGCCAACCUGACUGCGAGACAACGAGAUCCAGAGGACUCCCAGCGAACGGACGAGGGUGACAAUAGAGUGUGGUGUCAUGUUUGUGAGAGAGAAAACACUUUCGAGUGCCAGAACCCAAGGAGGUGCAAAUGGACAGAGCCAUACUGCGUUAUAGCGGCCGUGAAAAUAUUUCCACGUUUUUUCAUGGUUGCGAAGCAGUGCUCCGCUGGUUGUGCAGCGAUGGAGAGACCCAAGCCAGAGGAGAAGCGGUUUCUCCUGGAAGAGCCCAUGCCCUUCUUUUACCUCAAGUGUUGUAAAAUUCGCUACUGCAAUUUAGAGGGGCCACCUAUCAACUCAUCAGUGUUCAAAGAAUAUGCUGGGAGCAUGGGUGAGAGCUGUGGUGGGCUGUGGCUGGCCAUCCUCCUGCUGCUGGCCUCCAUUGCAGCCGGCCUCAGCCUGUCUUGAGCCACGGGACUGCCACAGACUGAGCCUUCCGGAGCAUGGACUCGCUCCAGACCGUUGUCACCUGUUGCAUUAAACUUGUUUUCUGUUGAUUACCUCUUGGUUUGACUUCCCAGGGUCUUGGGAUGGGAGAGUGGGGAUCAGGUGCAGUUGGCUCUUAACCCUCAAGGGUUCUUUAACUCACAUUCAGAGGAAGUCCAGAUCUCCUGAGUAGUGAUUUUGGUGACAAGUUUUUCUCUUUGAAAUCAAACCUUGUAACUCAUUUAUUGCUGAUGGCCACUCUUUUCCUUGACUCCCCUCUGCCUCUGAGGGCUUCAGUAUUGAUGGGGAGGGAGGCCUAAGUACCACUCAUGGAGAGUAUGUGCUGAGAUGCUUCCGACCUUUCAGGUGACGCAGGAACACUGGGGGAGUCUGAAUGAUUGGGGUGAAGACAUCCCUGGAGUGAAGGACUCCUCAGCAUGGGGGGCAGUGGGGCACACGUUAGGGCUGCCCCCAUUCCAGUGGUGGAGGCGCUGUGGAUGGCUGCUUUUCCUCAACCUUUCCUACCAGAUUCCAGGAGGCAGAAGAUAACUAAUUGUGUUGAAGAAACUUAGACUUCACCCACCAGCUGGCACAGGUGCACAGAUUCAUAAAUUCCCACACGUGUGUGUUCAACAUCUGAAACUUAGGCCAAGUAGAGAGCAUCAGGGUAAAUGGCGUUCAUUUCUCUGUUAAGAUGCAGCCAUCCAUGGGGAGCUGAGAAAUCAGACUCAAAGUUCCACCAAAAACAAAUACAAGGGGACUUCAAAAGUUCACGAAAAAAUUGAAUUAAAAGAUAAAAAUUAAAAAAUGUUUUAUUUCUCAGCAUGAGCUCCAUCAAGGUCGAGACGCUUCUGCAAGUAAUGGUACCAGCCAUUCAGUUCAUCCCUAAAGAAUUGGGCACCCUGGGAAUUUAACCAUGCCACUUCAGUCUUUGUGACGUUAUUAACUGAAGAAAAGUGGGUGCCCUUUAAAGAUUUUUUAAAAUUAUAAAACAGAAGUAACCAAAUCAGGCCUGGAAGGUGUAUGCCUAGUGAUUUCCCAUUGAAACUCUCACAAAACUGGCCUUGUUUGAUGAGAGGAAUGAGCAGGAGCAUUGUCAUGGUGGAGAAGGGCUCUCUGGUGAAGCUUUCCGGGGUGACGAUUUCCUGGGUGUUUUCCUGCUAAAUCGUUGGCUGACUUUCUCUAUACACUCUCAUAAUAAGAUGUUACUGUUCUUUGGCCCUCCAGAAAGUCAAUAAGCAAGAUGCCUUGAGCAUUCACAAAACGGUUGCCACGACCUUUGCCCUUGACAUGUCUGCUUUUACUCUGAUGGGACCACGCCCACCUCUAGGUAGUCAUUGCUUUGCUUGUGCUUUGCCUUCAGGAGUGUACUGGUUAAGCCACAUUUCAUCUCCGGCUAUAAUUAUAUGAAGAAAUGCUUCAGGAUCUUGAUUCCACUUGUUUAAAAUGGCCAUAGAACGCUUUUCUCUUAUCUGCAGCUGAGCUGGGAGAAAGUUUUGGCACCCACCGAGUGGACAGUUUACUCAACUUUAAUUUCAGUCAGAAUUGUGUAAGCUGAACACCUUGGGAUACCUACAGCGUUGGCUAUUGUUUCUGCUGCUAUUAAUCAGUCCUCUUAAAUUAGGGCACAAACAAGAUGAAUUGUUUCCUCACAGACUGAUGUGGCUGGCCUGCUGCUGUGGACUUCCUCUCCAACAUCAUCUCUUCUCUUCUUCCAAUGAGUUAUCCACUUACUUAA